AACAGUAACAGAGCCAUGGCUCAAGCUGGCCAGCGGGGCGGGCAGGCAGCAGACGCGGCAGGCGCGCGGGCCGCGGCAGGGGAGCCGGAGACCUCAGAAUUUUAAGAAAGAGAGGGGCGAGAGGUGGCCGAGGCGGGCGGGCUGGGGCACUGCGCUCUCCCAACGGCGCGGAUCCUCUUUGGAAAUUAAUAUUAAAAAAAAAAAAGCCGAGGACGCAGAGGGGAAGGUGGGGGGUAAGAGGGAAGGCGAGACACACACACACACACACACGCACACGCACACACGGACACACACACACGGAGAGAGAGAGAGAGAGAGACAGAGCCCCACAGUGAGAGGAAGGAAGGCAACAGUCGCCAGCAGCCGAUGUGAAGACCGGACUCCGUGCGCCCCUCGCCGCCUCUGCCUGGCCACAUCGAUGUUGUGUCCGCCGCCUGCUCGCCCGGAUCACGAUGAACGCGCAGCUGACCAUGGAAGCGAUCGGCGAGCUGCACGGGGUGAGCCAUGAGCCGGUGCCCGCCCCUGCCGACCUGCUGGGCGGCAGCCCCCACGCGCGCAGCUCCGUGGCGCACCGCGGCAGCCACCUGCCCCCCGCGCACCCGCGCUCCAUGGGCAUGGCGUCCCUGCUGGACGGCGGCAGCGGCGGCGGAGAUUACCACCACCACCACCGGGCCCCUGAGCACAGCCUGGCCGGCCCCCUGCAUCCCACCAUGACCAUGGCCUGCGAGACUCCCCCAGGUAUGAGCAUGCCCACCACCUACACCACCUUGACCCCUCUGCAGCCGCUGCCUCCCAUCUCCACAGUCUCGGACAAGUUCCCCCACCAUCACCACCACCACCAUCACCACCACCACCCGCACCACCACCAGCGCCUGGCGGGCAACGUGAGCGGUAGCUUCACGCUCAUGCGGGAUGAGCGCGGGCUGGCCUCCAUGAAUAACCUCUAUACCCCCUACCACAAGGACGUGGCCGGCAUGGGCCAGAGCCUCUCGCCCCUCUCCAGCUCCGGUCUGGGCAGCAUCCACAACUCCCAGCAAGGGCUCCCCCACUAUGCCCACCCGGGGGCCGCCAUGCCCACCGACAAGAUGCUCACCCCCAACGGCUUCGAAGCCCACCACCCGGCCAUGCUCGGCCGCCACGGGGAGCAGCACCUCACGCCCACCUCGGCCGGCAUGGUGCCCAUCAACGGCCUUCCUCCGCACCAUCCCCACGCCCACCUGAACGCCCAGGGCCACGGGCAACUCCUGGGCACAGCCCGGGAGCCCAACCCUUCGGUGACCGGCGCGCAGGUCAGCAAUGGAAGUAAUUCAGGGCAGAUGGAAGAGAUCAAUACCAAAGAGGUGGCGCAGCGUAUCACCACCGAGCUCAAGCGCUACAGCAUCCCACAGGCCAUCUUCGCGCAGAGGGUGCUCUGCCGCUCCCAGGGGACCCUCUCGGACCUGCUGCGCAACCCCAAACCCUGGAGCAAACUCAAAUCCGGCCGGGAGACCUUCCGGAGGAUGUGGAAGUGGCUGCAGGAGCCGGAGUUCCAGCGCAUGUCCGCGCUCCGCUUAGCAGCAUGCAAAAGGAAAGAACAAGAACAUGGGAAGGAUAGAGGCAACACACCCAAAAAGCCCAGGUUGGUCUUCACAGAUGUCCAGCGUCGAACUCUACAUGCAAUAUUCAAGGAAAAUAAGCGUCCAUCCAAAGAAUUGCAAAUCACCAUUUCCCAGCAGCUGGGGUUGGAGCUGAGCACUGUCAGCAACUUCUUCAUGAACGCAAGAAGGAGGAGUCUGGACAAGUGGCAGGACGAGGGCAGCUCCAAUUCAGGCAACUCAUCUUCUUCAUCAAGCACUUGUACCAAAGCAUGAAGGAAGAACCACAAACUAAAACCUCGGUGGAAAAGCUUUAAAUUAAAAAAAAUUUUUAAAAGACCAGGACCUCAAGAUAGCAGGUUUAUACUUAGAAAUAUUUGAAGAAAAAAAAGCGUUAUUUAUAGUCCAAAGAAACCAAAGACUUAGCUCACCUGCAUUCUGACUUUGUUUGGAGACACACACUUCAGCAGGGCGGCGACUUGGCAAGACAAAUGAUGAGCAGGAAAACACCACUGGAUCUCACACCUUCAAUCCAUGACCAUCCUCGCUGUGCUUGGCUGUUUAGUGGUUUGGAGCAUAGUGAUUUUGAGCCAUUGAGCGGACAUCUUUUAAGAUCGAACUUUCUCAUCUGUUCUACCAUGCCACGAAGGUGUAUGGUGUCUCAGUACUACCACCACCAGUGGUUACAGACUUAGGCAGAGCUGGUCUUCAGAAAUGGUUGUUCUAUAGGAGUGCAACCAACAUGGUAUGGGGUUGUCUGAGUUCAUUGGAUUAGGAGUGUGAUUUUGCUCGUCUAGCCUAACGUUUGAACCUGCCAGGCCCGCAACCUAAAUGCAGAUUCAAACCCAGCAAAGAAAAUUUGAAUGACACCUAAACCAGUGCAUUCUCUUUGUUUGUUAAGGAAUGUUCAGAUAUUUUUUAAGAAAUGAAACAUGAGUCCAUCCAUUAAAAAAAUCACCUAGGUACCAAAGAACACACUUAAUAUUAUAGUGCAGGUAUUUUAUUGCAAUGAUUUUAAUAACCAAAGCUAUUUUUACACAAGAUACUAUGAAAAGUUAUACGUAUGAACUGAUCUAGCUGUAAUACACAUGCCACAUAGAAUCAUGACUAUUAUUUAUGACUCUUGAAGCAUUUGAAAUAUGAGUUUUCAGAACUGGCAAGAAAGAAUGUAGCUUCAGGGAAGCAAUUAAUAUCAUGGCAGAGAGGUCGAUGCAGUACACGUGUACAUCCAGAUGGCACACUCCUUUUCAGGAUCCAUAAAUGUCACUUAAGUAGAGAGAUAGACAUGGUUCCAUAAUCUGUUCCUAGCUGAGAAAACCUGAGGAUCUUUCCAAAGUAGUACCCCAUUUUUACACUAGAAAACUAAAUUUAACAGGGAGGGUAACUAAAUUAGAAAAUUUGUUCAAAGUAAUGCUUUUUAGUAAAAGGUCACUAAAUAAAGAACUAUCCUUAGAUUAAUUGACUUAUAUUUGCUUUAUGCAUCUGGCACCAAAAACCUCUUUUAAAUACUUUACAAAUACAAAUAAAGUUUAAAAAAACAACAUUAUUAUUCAAAUGAGCUAUUCAGUACUUAUAACUAUCCUAAAAAGUUAUCAAAUUAACUUAUUGCCAAUCCCAGAAAUUUUAUGACUUGGACGUCAACAAAACAGCAGGUGCAACUGAGAAAUGGUGGAAUUGGUGGAACUGUAUAGAAAAAAGCCAGUGUUCUGGUGGACGACAAGACUUUUGAUCUAUUGGUAUUAAUCAAUUUAUGGAACUAAGAAUAGCCUCCAAAGCAUUCUGCCUUCUUUCUUGCUACUGCAUUUAGCUGGAAAUUUUAUAAUAUAGAUUUUGCUCUCUAACAGGGACAGAUUAAAAACUAGACCUGAGCUUACAAAUACAAAAUUUUAAAUUUCUAUUUGUCCAAAUCACUUAACCAGAGCUGUAGAAGUCAAAGUCAAAAAAAAAAUGAAGUCGUAUUAGUGGUACCCCAGUGAAUCACUUGAUUCCCAGAAAAAUUCUCUCUGAAUUCAGUUGGACUGUAACUUAUCUAAGUGGAUGCCCCUUAUGCCAUUAGGUAAAGAAUUGGAUACUGUAAGUUAAUUACCACCCCUACUUAGAACUAUGAAAUUAAAUGUUAUCCUAAUGAUAAGUUGUUUUAUUGAGAUUCAUUAAAAAUGCCAAAGAACAAAACUGAACCAUCUUGACACAAAACAUAACUCCUUAGCAUCAAAUCUCAGCACCUUGUCUAGGUCUGUAACAGGCAGGCAACUAGAGAGGUAAAGCAAAACCAACAAGCCAUCUAUCUGUGUCUCCUUCAUGUCUGCUGUCGAAUGAGAAGAGGAAACCAACAUAUACUUCUCUUUUGAUGAAAUACUUCAUUUGCCUUGACAUGUUUUGUUUUUUGUUUUUAAUUUCACCCACAACUCCAGCUUAAAAAUUUCCCUUCUAAAUAUGGCACAAUUAUAGUUCAGCUAUUGAAAGAGACCAUUUAAAUGGCCACCCUUCAAGAUUUACUAAAAAAUAGAAUCUUGUCAAUGACAUAAACAAAAAGGAAAAAACUGAUUAACAUUUUCUCUCUCUCCAGGGAUGGAGGGAGCCGGGGAUACAGCUACAUAAUGUAUUUAUAAUUUAGGAGGGAGGAAAGCCUUAUUUAUUUAAAACGUGAUAAUUCUAAAUGCAGGGAAAUUCAAGCUGUGUCUACACACAAUCUUACCAAAUUCAAUACCCCAAGAAAAGAAUAGCAGAAUUCAGACAACCAUGUUUUUUAUUUGUUGCUAGUAUAUAUUACCCCCAAAA